AUGGCACAUGCAGCGCAAGUAGGUCUACAAGACGCUACUUCCCCUAUCAUAGAAGAGCUUAUCACCUUUCAUGAUCACGCCCUCAUAAUCAUUUUCCUUAUCUGCUUCCUAGUCCUGUAUGCCCUUUUCCUAACACUCACAACAAAACUAACUAAUACUAACAUCUCAGACGCUCAGGAAAUAGAAACCGUCUGAACUAUCCUGCCCGCCAUCAUCCUAGUCCUCAUCGCCCUCCCAUCCCUACGCAUCCUUUACAUAACAGACGAGGUCAACGAUCCCUCCCUUACCAUCAAAUCAAUUGGCCACCAAUGGUACUGAACCUACGAGUACACCGACUACGGCGGACUAAUCUUCAACUCCUACAUACUUCCCCCAUUAUUCCUAGAACCAGGCGACCUGCGACUCCUUGACGUUGACAAUCGAGUAGUACUCCCGAUUGAAGCCCCCAUUCGUAUAAUAAUUACAUCACAAGACGUCUUGCACUCAUGAGCUGUCCCCACAUUAGGCUUAAAAACAGAUGCAAUUCCCGGACGUCUAAACCAAACCACUUUCACCGCUACACGACCGGGGGUAUACUACGGUCAAUGCUCUGAAAUCUGUGGAGCAAACCACAGUUUCAUGCCCAUCGUCCUAGAAUUAAUUCCCCUAAAAAUCUUUGAAAUAGGGCCCGUAUUUACCCUAUAG